CUUUUGUGACUUUUGGGAGAGCUGCCAAAAGUGAAACUUAGUGCCUCAGACAAGCAGGGGCAAGUCUGCUAAGGAAGCUGUGGCCAGAAGCACAGAUCAGAAACACGAUGGCUCUGUUAACAGCCGAAACAUUCCGCUUACAGUUUAACAACAAGCGCCGCCUCAGAAGGCCUUACUACCCGAGGAAGGCCCUCUUGUGUUACCAGCUGACGCCGCAGAAUGGCUCCACGCCCACGAGAGGCUACUUUGAAAACAAGAAAAAGUGCCAUGCAGAAAUUUGCUUUAUUAACGAGAUCAAGUCCAUGGGACUGGACGAAACGCAGUGCUACCAAGUCACCUGUUACCUCACGUGGAGCCCCUGCUCCUCCUGUGCCUGGGAGCUGGUUGACUUCAUCAAGGCUCACGACCAUCUGAACCUGGGCAUCUUCGCCUCCCGCCUGUACUACCACUGGUGCAAGCCCCAGCAGAAGGGGCUGCGGCUUCUGUGUGGAUCCCAGGUCCCGGUGGAGGUCAUGGGCUUCCCAGAGUUUGCUGACUGCUGGGAAAACUUUGUGGACCACGAGAAACCGCUUUCCUUCAACCCCUAUAAGAUGUUAGAGGAGCUAGAUAAAAACAGUCGAGCCAUAAAGCGACGGCUUGAGAGGAUAAAGGGGCUCCUUCUUGUUCUUUUAGAUUCCAGGGGUACGUGCGCAGGGUCGUUACAUGGAUAUAUUGUGUGAUGCUGAGGUCUGAGUCACCCAAUCUACUGGAACAUAGCACCCAAUAGCAGUCCUGAAGUGUGGAUGUUUUAGAGAAUGACUUAAGAAGUUUGCAGCUUGGACCCGUAUCCCACUCAUUAUCAAGAAGCAACUCAAGAUGACUUUCCCUGGGGCAUGUCAGUUGCCUCAUAGCCUGCUGGUCCUGUAAGCAAGCACUAAGCUCCACAGUGCCAGUUCCUUGCCCCAACCUGGCCCCAUCCAAGUACAGAAGACCUUCCUUUCCUCCUUUUUCCAUAUUGCUUUCUGUUCUAAGUGGGUGAAUAAUUUUAUAAUUGAAAAAAUAAAGAUAAAGUCUGUAAAUCCAGCCGGGUACGGUGGCUCACGCCUGUAAUCCUAGCACUUUGGGAGGCUGAGAUGCUCGGCCAAUAAAUUUCUAUUGUUUAUGAA